AGCAGUCUGGGUUGGGCAGAAGGCAGAAAACCAGCAGAGUCACAGAGGAGAUGGCCAACUGCCAAAUAGCCAUCUUGUACCAGAGAUUCCAGAGAGUGGUCUUUGGAAUUUCCCAACUCCUUUGCUUCAGUGCCCUGAUCUCUGAACUAACAAACCAGAAAGAAGUGGCAGCAUGGACUUAUCAUUACAGCACAAAAGCAUACUCAUGGAAUAUUUCCCGUAAAUACUGCCAGAAUCGCUACACAGACUUAGUGGCCAUCCAGAAUAAAAAUGAAAUUGAUUACCUCAAUAAGGUCCUACCCUACUACAGCUCCUACUACUGGAUUGGGAUCCGAAAGAACAAUAAGACAUGGACAUGGGUGGGAACCAAAAAGGCUCUCACCAACGAGGCUGAGAACUGGGCUGAUAAUGAACCUAACAACAAAAGGAACAACGAGGACUGCGUGGAGAUAUACAUCAAGAGUCCGUCAGCCCCUGGCAAGUGGAAUGAUGAGCACUGCUUGAAGAAAAAGCACGCAUUGUGUUACACAGCCUCCUGCCAGGACAUGUCCUGCAGCAAACAAGGAGAGUGCCUCGAGACCAUCGGGAACUACACCUGCUCCUGUUACCCUGGAUUCUAUGGGCCAGAAUGUGAAUACGUGAGAGAGUGUGGAGAACUUGAGCUCCCUCAACACGUGCUCAUGAACUGCAGCCACCCUCUGGGAAACUUCUCUUUUAACUCGCAGUGCAGCUUCCACUGCACUGACGGGUACCAAGUAAAUGGGCCCAGCAAGCUGGAAUGCUUGGCUUCUGGAAUCUGGACAAAUAAGCCUCCACAGUGUUUAGCUGCCCAGUGCCCACCCCUGAAGAUUCCUGAACGAGGAAACAUGACCUGCCUUCAUUCUGCAAAAGCAUUCCAGCAUCAGUCUAGCUGCAGCUUCAGUUGUGAAGAGGGAUUUGCAUUAGUUGGACCGGAAGUGGUGCAAUGCACAGCCUCGGGGGUAUGGACAGCCCCAGCCCCAGUGUGUAAAGCUGUGCAGUGUCAGCACCUGGAAGCCCCCAGUGAAGGAACCAUGGACUGUGUUCAUCCGCUCACUGCUUUUGCCUAUGGCUCCAGCUGUAAAUUUGAGUGCCAGCCCGGCUACAGAGUGAGGGGCUUGGACAUGCUCCGCUGCAUUGACUCUGGACACUGGUCUGCACCCUUGCCAACCUGUGAGGCUAUUUCGUGUGAGCCGCUGGAGAGUCCUGUCCACGGAAGCAUGGAUUGCUCUCCAUCCUUGAGAGCGUUUCAGUAUGACACCAACUGUAGCUUCCGCUGUGCUGAAGGUUUCAUGCUGAGAGGAGCCGAUAUAGUUCGGUGUGAUAACUUGGGACAGUGGACAGCACCAGCCCCAGUCUGUCAAGCUUUGCAGUGCCAGGAUCUCCCAGUUCCAAAUGAGGCCCGGGUGAACUGCUCCCACCCCUUCGGUGCCUUUAGGUACCAGUCAGUCUGCAGCUUCACCUGCAAUGAAGGCUUGCUCCUGGUGGGAGCAAGUGUGCUACAGUGCUUGGCUACUGGAAACUGGAAUUCUGUUCCUCCAGAAUGCCAAGCCAUUCCCUGCACACCUUUGCUAAGCCCUCAGAAUGGAACAAUGACCUGUGUUCAACCUCUUGGAAGUUCCAGUUAUAAAUCCACAUGUCAAUUCAUCUGUGACGAGGGAUAUUCUUUGUCUGGACCAGAAAGAUUGGAUUGUACUCGAUCGGGACGCUGGACAGACUCCCCACCAAUGUGUGAAGCCAUCAAGUGCCCAGAACUCUUUGCCCCAGAGCAGGGCAGCCUGGAUUGUUCUGACACUCGUGGAGAAUUCAAUGUUGGCUCCACCUGCCAUUUCUCUUGUGACAACGGCUUUAAGCUGGAGGGGCCCAAUAAUGUGGAAUGCACAACUUCUGGAAGAUGGUCAGCUACUCCACCAACCUGCAAAGGCAUAGCAUCACUUCCUACUCCAGGGGUGCAAUGUCCAGCCCUCACCACUCCUGGGCAGGGAACCAUGUACUGUAGGCAUCAUCCGGGAACCUUUGGUUUUAAUACCACUUGUUACUUUGGCUGCAACGCUGGAUUCACACUCAUAGGAGACAGCACUCUCAGCUGCAGACCUUCAGGACAAUGGACAGCAGUAACUCCAGCAUGCAGAGCUGUGAAAUGCUCAGAACUACAUGUUAAUAAGCCAAUAGCGAUGAACUGCUCCAACCUCUGGGGAAACUUCAGUUAUGGAUCAAUCUGCUCUUUCCAUUGUCUAGAGGGCCAGUUACUUAAUGGCUCUGCACAAACAGCAUGCCAAGAGAAUGGCCACUGGUCAACUACCGUGCCAACCUGCCAAGCAGGACCAUUGACUAUCCAGGAAGCCCUGACUUACUUUGGUGGAGCGGUGGCUUCUACGAUAGGUCUGAUAAUGGGUGGGACGCUCCUGGCUUUGCUAAGAAAGCGUUUCAGACAAAAAGAUGAUGGGAAAUGCCCCUUGAAUCCUCACAGCCACCUAGGAACAUAUGGAGUUUUUACAAACGCUGCAUUUGACCCGAGUCCUUAAGGUGGUGAUGAUGUGGCCUUGCCUGCAAAGCAGAAGUCAGGACUGCUGAAAAAUGUUUACGAACUGUUAUGGAGUCAAUUCCCUAUGCUACCUGCUGGAAAAACAAAAAUAAUCUGAUGCUAUCCCUCUCCCAAAAAGUGGGUAGUUGAGUGUCCUACAAAAAGCCUGAAUGGCAGAAUAUUCGAAAUCUAGAAAGAAAAGAUUAUGCUGCGCCUCAGGGUGUAGAUAUGAUGAGCAAUUUUUUUCUUUCUUUUAUUUUUUUAAGGAAAUGAUAAUUAUUUAAAUUUCUUUGGUCUCAUUUCCAGAGACCUGUCCUUUUCCUGGUCUCCUCAUUCAGCCUCCAUAUGAUCCUGUUGUGAACAUCAAGUUUCCUGCUACACUGGACUUAACUAUAAUGCAUUUGCUGCAGGUUUCCAUAAACACCCAUGAAUCAAAGACAUGGAAUUACCUUAGAUUAGCUCUGGACCAGCCUGUUGGACCCGCUCUGGACCAACCCUGUUUCCUGAGUUUGGGAUUGUGGUACAAUCUCAAAUUCUCAACCUACCACCCCUUCCUGUCCCACCUCUUCUCUUCCUGUAACACAAGCCACAGAAGCCAGGAGCAAAUGUUUCUGCAGUAGUCUCUGUGCUUUGACUCACCUGUUACUUGAAAUACCAGUGAACCAAAGAGACUGGAGCAUCUGACUCACAAGAAGACCAGACUGUGGAGAAAUAAAAAUACCUCUUUAUUUUUUGAUUGAAGGAAGGUUUUCUCCACUUUGUUGGAAAGCAGGUGGCAUCUCUAAUUGGAAGAAAUUCCUGUAGCAUCUUCUGGAGUCUCCAGUGGUUGCUGUUGAUGAGGCCUCUUGGACCUCUGCUCUGAGGCUUCCAGAGAGUCCUCUGGAUGGCACCAGAGGCUGCAGAAGGCCAAGAAUCAAGCUAGAAGGCCACAUGUCACCGUGGACCUUCCUGCCACCAGUCACUGUCCCUCAAAUGACCCAAAGACCAAUAUUCAAAUGCGUAAUUAAAAGAAUUUUCCCCAAA